GCCGUCGGAGCCCUUGCACGCCUGCUCUCUUGUAGCUUCUCUCAGCCUAGCCCAGCAUCACUAUGGUGGACGCUUUCCUGGGCACCUGGAAGCUAGUGGACAGCAAGAAUUUCGAUGACUACAUGAAGUCACUCGGUGUGGGUUUUGCUACCAGGCAGGUGGCCAGCAUGACCAAGCCUACCACAAUCAUCGAAAAGAAUGGGGACAUUCUCACCCUAAAAACACACAGCACCUUCAAGAACACAGAGAUCAGCUUUAAGUUGGGGGUGGAGUUCGAUGAGACAACAGCAGAUGACAGGAAGGUCAAGUCCAUUGUGACACUGGAUGGAGGGAAACUUGUUCACCUGCAGAAAUGGGACGGGCAAGAGACCACACUUGUGCGGGAGCUAAUUGAUGGAAAACUCAUCCUGAUGGAAAAACUGCAACUCAGAAAUGUAAAGUGAGUCGACCAAGGCUAAAGCGGCAAAACCACUAUACUUUAUAACACAGAGUUUGGCACUAUUUCCACUUUGUUCUCUCUCAAAGAUGAAGGCUCAGGAGGAGGGAAGAUAAAAACAAAUCACUGGAGAGUCCUGGCAUGCUGGAACAUGGACUCUAGCUAGCAAGAAGGGCUCAAGGAGGUGGCCUUCUCCUAGACCUCAACUUUGAUGCAAAAGCUGUUUUGCAGCCUGAACAAAGACAAUCCAAUCCUCCAGCAAAUGGCGUCAUUUUCCCUACGUGUCUAGCCUUGAGCUACAGAACAAAAGAACAAUCACAUCCGAAGUUGUAGUUCGCCUGGUUGCGGUGGCUCACGCCUGUGAUCCCAGCACUUUGGGAGGCCAAGGUGGGUGGAUCACCUGAGGUCAGGAGGUCGAGACUAGCCUGACCAACAUGAAGAAACCCCAUCUCUACUAAAAAUACAAAAUUAGCUGGGCGUGGUGGCACAUGCCUGUAAUCCCAGCUACUCGGGAGGCUGAGGCAGGAGAAUCGCUUGAGCGUGGGAGGCGGAGGUUUUGGUGAGCCAAGAUCGCGCCACUGCACUCCAGCCUGGGCAACAAGAGCGAAACUCUGUCUCAAAACAAAACAAAACAAAACACGCACACACAAAAACAAAAUUAGCCGGGCGUGGUGGCACAUGCCUGUAAUCCCAGCUACUCGGGAGGCUGAGGCAGGAGAAUUGCUUGAACCCGGAGGCAGAGGUUGGGGUCAGCCAAGAUUGUGCCAUUGCACUCCAGCCUGGGCAACAAGAUGGAAACUCCGUCUCAAAAAAAAAAAAAAGGUUGUAGUUCAAAAGCAAAGUUGGGAGUUGGGGUGGGGGAAGACUGAGAGCCAGAAGAUGAACCAAGCUUCUGCUCUCUCAACUUCAUUCAAGUGAGAAGGGAAACAGAAGAUAAUGGGUUAAAAAAAAAUGACAUGGAUUCAAGUAUCAGAUGGAAAUAGAAAAUUAAACAUAAAACAGUUUUUAAAUGGCAUAGGAGUGUGAGCCCAUGGCGCAGGUCAAGGGGGCACUGGAAGGAAGCCACUGGUCAAACAUCUCAAAGACUGCUCUCUAGGAAAAGCACAUAUCCCUUGUUAGAGCAGCUAGUCUACCCAUUUUCACUAUAGUUCUGAAACAGGAUAGCAGCAGCCCAGUGUGACAGAAAAACAAAAAUAAAAGCAAAAACUGAAAAAAGA